ACUUCGCCGCCCGCGUCAGGCCACACCGGUGGUCUGGGCUGGGGACCGCGGGUCGGGUCCGGUUUCCAGGGGGUUCCUGGUGCUCGAGGCUGGCGGCGAGGAAGGUACUGGCUGAGGGCCCGCGUCGGGCCCGCCCUGCGCACGCGUCGUGAUCAAGGGCGCCGGCCGCCGGCCGCGCCCCCAAGCCUCUGUUUCUCAGAGUGCGUCGUGGGCGUCCAGGGGACUGUCGGGCCGCGGCGGGAGCCAUGCGCUCUCCCACCGUGCGGCAGCCCAGGAGGCUGCGCGCUGGGCGUUCCACGUCCAUGAUGGCCGGGGAGACUGAGGCGCGGGGCGGCCCCGGGACGCUGCUGGCGGGGAAAGGCUGGGUGGUCCACGCCUUUCUUCCCUCCCAGCUGCGGGUUCCGCUGGCGGCGGUGGCGCUGACAAGCCCGCGUCGGGGAAGCAGGGGAGUCCCUGCUCACACAGACCGCGCCCUCACGGAGGGAGGCCGCUUCCUAGACCUCGCCUAGUCGUCUUUCCUCUCCCUGCCCUGGGGGGGUUGCGGGGGUCAGUGCAAACUCCUGCGUCCAGGGCACUGGUGAGCUCCCGAGUUCGGGCAGCCAGGGGGCUGAGGUCCCGAAGGAGGCUCCGAGGGGAGAGUCCUGCGUGUGCAAAACCUGGGAGGGGAGCCGAAGCCCAGGUGCUUCUGGGACUGAGCUCUCUCGAUGUGGAGCUGGAGUAGAGGGGAUGUGUGCGGCUGCAGUAUCAGGCGAGGGAGUGGGCUUUAUCUCGAGGGCGUCGGGAGACAUAGAAGUUUUGAACAGAAUCAGGACAUCCUCUGAGGACUUUAAAACGGUUCCACCGUUUGUUGCGUGGAGAACAGACAUGCAGGGGUGUCGGCAUGAAGGGAAGAACCGACUGCCACAGUCUGGGCAGCAGUGGAGGUGGGCGACCAGGUGAAUUCUGGUGGAUCUGCGGAUGCAUCAGGUGUGGGCUGUUUGAAGAACUAAGUACCCCAUGUUGUUCAGCCUGAGCGCCUGGAAGAAGAGAGCUGCUGUAGAUAGAAAGGAGAAUUGAAAGGAAAGCAGGUUUCCUUCAGGGGAAAGAUCAAGAGUCUGGGAUGUCCCAGGACCAGAUGGCCUUUGAGGAUGUGGCUGUGUACUUCUCCCAGGAGGAGUGGGGGCUCCUGGACACAGCCCAGAGGGCCCUGUACCGCCGCGUGAUGCUAGACAACUUCGCACUUGUGGCCUCGCUGGGACUCUCCACCUCUCGACCUCGUGUGGUCAUCCAACUGGAGCGUGGCGAGGAGCCCUGGGUUCCCAGUGGAACGGACACAACCCUGUCCAGGACCACCUACAGGAGGCGCAACCCUGGUUCCUGGAGUUUGACAGAGGAUAGAGAUGUUUCUGGAGAAUGGCCACGAGCUUUCCCAGAUACCCCACCUGGGAUGACUACUAGCGUCUUCCCUGUUGCCGGUGCCUGCCACAGUGUAAAAAGCCUGCAGAGACAACGGGGUGCCUCCCCAUCUCGGGAGAGAAAACCCACGGGGGUGUCGGUGAUCUACUGGGAGAGGCUCCUGCUAGGCUCAGGCAGUGGGCAAGCCAGCGUCAGCCUGCGACUGACCUCCCCGCUUAGGCCUCCCGAGGGCGUCCGGCUUAGAGAAAAGACACUCACAGAGCAUGCGUUGCUGGGGAGGCAGCCCAGGACGCCUGAGCGGCAGAAACCAUGUGCACAGGAGGUCCCUGGGAGAACCUUUGGGAGCGCCCAGGACCUGGAGGCUGCCGGCGGUCGGGGACAUCACCGAAUGGGUGCAGUUUGGCAGGAGCCUCAUAGACUCCUCGGUGGCCAGGAGCCCUCGACCUGGGACGAGCUGGGCGAGGCUCUUCACGCUGGGGAGAAGUCCUUCGAAUGCAGGGCGUGCAGCAAAGUGUUCGUGAAGAGCUCCGACCUCCUCAAGCACCUACGCACCCACACCGGGGAGCGGCCCUACGAGUGCGCCCAGUGCGGCAAGGCCUUCAGCCAGACGUCGCACUUGACGCAGCACCAGCGCAUCCACAGCGGCGAGACGCCCUACGCGUGCCCCGUGUGCGGCAAGGCCUUCCGGCAUAGCUCCUCGCUGGUGCGGCACCAGCGCAUCCACACGGCCGAGAAGUCCUUCCGCUGCUCCGAGUGCGGCAAGGCCUUCAGCCACGGCUCCAACCUCAGCCAGCACCGCAAGAUCCACGCGGGUGGGCGUCCUUAUGCUUGCGCACAGUGUGGCCGCCGCUUCUGCCGCAACUCGCACCUGAUCCAGCACGAGCGUACGCACACAGGCGAGAAGCCCUUCGUGUGCGCGCUCUGCGGUGCUGCCUUCAGCCAGGGCUCCUCGCUCUUUAAGCACCAGCGCGUGCACACAGGCGAGAAGCCCUUCGCCUGCCCACAGUGCGGCCGCGCCUUUAGCCACAGCUCCAACCUCACCCAGCACCAGCUCCUGCACACGGGCGAGCGGCCCUUCCGCUGCGUGGACUGUGGCAAGGCCUUCGCCAAGGGCGCCGUGCUGCUCAGCCACCGGCGCAUUCACACGGGCGAGAAGCCCUUCGUGUGUACGCAGUGUGGCCGCGCCUUCCGUGAGCGCCCGGCCCUCUUCCACCACCAGAGGAUCCAUACCGGCGAGAAGACCGUCCGGCGAUCCAGGGCCAGCCUGCACCCCCAGGCCAGGUCUGUUGCCGGGGCAUCAUCAGAAGGUGCGCCAGCGAAGGAAACCGAGCCCACUCCCGCCUCGGGCCCAGCCGCCGUCUCGCAGCCAGCGGAGGUCUGAGGUCACAGGUUGCAGCCCUGGCCUUCUGUGAAUCCCUUCCACAGCUAAAGGGCAUAUGUCCUCUGCAGAUCCACAGCAGAGAAAAAGUCCCGUGCUUGCUAGUCAGGGACAAGGGAGGCCCUUUGGCUGUGAUUUCAUUUGCACGUGGGGACAGGAUUUGCCAGUUCACCCACAGAUCACACCUCCAUCCCCAAAGAGGUAGCACUGCAGCAACAUCAGGGGGAGGACGUGGUGGCUGAACUCUAGUGGGGCCGAGACUAUUCAGAGCCAGUAGGAGGCCGACAGUCACAGCACUGCACUGUGGUGCGGCUUCAUGUGAUAUGACAGUGGAUGCUAAGGUGAGAGGGAUGCAGGCAUGGGUUGGGGGUGGCCCAGAGAAACUUAUGACAGCUGUACACAAACUGGCCGCUGGAGAGAUGCCCGCUGAGGGUAUUCUCCCCUCAACCCACUGCCUCUGUUCAUCCAAGACUUCCUAGGGGCCAGCCUAGCAGACAAGAGACCACAAGGGACUGGGGAUCAGGGUCUGGGCUCUGUCAGCCGCCACCUCUGGGAAAGAGAAAAGGUUUGGGUCCACUGAACAUCAUGUUUGUAGACGCUGACAGGUGGGGUCCUAAUGAGAGCCAACACAUGCUCACUGCCAGCUCCUGUCCUGAGUACUGGGAAGUUUCUCCUGAAGCCCUGUGAGAUGGCUCUGUGGCUGGUAUCCCGACUUGGAAGAUGAGGAAACUGAGGCACACGGCCUGGCCUGGCUUCACACACAUAGCCGACUCAGGAGAGGGAUGCCCAUGGGGGAACAUGUGACUCUCAGCAUUGGAAGGACAGAGCUAGGAUGAUGGCUUUCCGGUGGCACUCGUUCAGGUUUUUGCCCAAGUCUCAGCUUGGCCAAGGCCUGUCACUGACUGGUUUACCAAAGUCGAUGUGAGGAGGAGGCUUUAUACCUGAGGGGAUGAUGUUAACUUCAGACAAGAUGGAGCUGCUCACUUUUGCCGGGUUUGGUGGCCACUUCACCCCCAACCCUGUCUCACCCCCAUUAUCCCUCCUCAAUUGGAGGCUGGACAGAGCUGAAUAGGAAAGACUUGCUAUUGCCUAAGGCUAUGUGUGACACCCUCCUGAGGACCUCCCCACCCCAGUGUAAUGGCCCUUCAUGGCAGGGACAGAAAGGUGGACUGGGGGCCAUUUGCUUCCUGUGGCCUUCAGCAGACCAGGCCCUGUCCCUACCUGGAGCCUCACCUCCAAGGAAAUUCAUGUUCUCCUUAAUGGAAAAAAAAAAAAAAAGACUACCAUCUGCAACUCAGAGUAGGUGUUGCAGUUUCCUGUACAGCAGUUUGGACCUCCAGAGCACAGCCUCUUGUCCCUACUCCAGAGCAUGGUUCAGUCUUAAUAGCAGUUCAAGAGCUUCUCUGAUAAAGGUUUCUUUUUAAACAUUUGUGUGAACGGUAGCAACCUGACACCUAUUUCACCCUCAUACAAUGCAGAUGGUAUUGAACAUACCCUGACAUGCCAUCAGCGUUUGUCAUCAUCACAGAAGUUCCUGGACUUGGCUUCAACCUGGGUACCCUCAAGAGGCCACAGAGUAGAGAUACAGCCUGUCUGCAGCCCAGGGAGGGAGUGGGAUACCUGUAUCCUUUUCAGGGUCAGAGGUGGGUUGGGGUAGCCAGGAGCUGGAUGAACUGGGAUAGAGUGGGGCUGUCUGGAGCAGCAGCCCUGCUAGAUGAGUCCUGGUGGAUCCUGGCAAUGGGAGGAUGGUAGGUGGAGAAACCAAGGCAGGGCUGUGUUCCUUCUGCUGCUGAGAUAGAGGGUGUGGCCAUGUGUGAUGACCCUGCAAGGUUGACUCCAACCAGUGGGCACUCCAUCCCAUGGCUUCCAAAAUCCUGCAGCUAUCCUGCCCUAUACACAAAGAGCCCAGAUCCAGGCCCCACACACUUGAUAUUGGGGCCAGACUCUUCCACCUGUGAAACCUCACAGGUUCCUGCAGGGAGUGGAGACACACAGAACCUAGCUCCCCUGGAGCCUGCAAGACUUGGGCCACCAGAAUCCCAGUAGGUCCCUGAACCAUUGUCCCCCAGUAAGUCUGCAGAGCUGUGAAAUGCAGACAAUAACCCUUCCCUGCCUGAAAGAGCACUUUUCUGGGGAGCCCAUGGGAGUCAGGAGCAAAAGCAUCUGUCAAACAAGUAGAUACCCAGAGAGUCACGUGAAAUCAUUUCUAUGCCUCUGACAGACGCUUCUUGAGCGAAGUUUCUGCCCUGAGCCCGCCUGACCCCUUAGGCUGGGCUCAGUACCCUACCUUGUCUUCCCACCAGCCGCCUCCCUCCAUCAAGUUCCUUUCCACGUCUGCUUGUGCCCCUGUUGUCCCUCAGUUUGUCCACCCUCCUCCAAUCUUCCCCUCCCCAAACCCAUGACUGAUCAGUGGCCCCCAACCUAGGCUCCCACCUCCAUGCAGGUCUUGGCCCCUCGGCUGACCUCCCUCCAACCUCCCCCUCUGCUCUUAAUUUUGAAUAGGUAGUGACUGUAAAAGUAUCCCUGGGCUUCUAUGUCAAAAGGUCAGACUGAACACAUGCAUCUCACUGGGCUCAGAAAUCCACUGAAACCACAGAGGGGAGUAUUUAAAACACAUAACCCACAAGUAUGAGGAUGGUGACAGAGGAGUCAGGAGCAAUGGCAUUCCUAAGCUAGAAGUGGGUGAGAGCUGUCACUAAGUUAGGGAAGGCAAAAUACUACGUGGCGACUUGGCGAAGAGGAGAGAGUUCCCACCAGGCUGACUCCAGAACCGCAGAAGGCUGAGAACCAGCAGCCCAGAGACGGGAGACCUAUAUCAAAGCUGCCUGGGGAACAACUACUGAAGAAGCCCUUAACGCCCCAGUGCUCUCCCCACAUGGUGGAGGGUGAAAGUUUUUGUUUUUUUUUCCUUCUGGGACUCUGCAUAGUCCCAGAGAAAAGGCCUAAGCACCUCAUCCCCAAAAACAACCUGAGGAGGCCGUUGGAAAGCUCCGAGUUGACAAGUCUCAUCCACGCACAUGCUCGGUGCUUCCAAUCGGUGAUCAAGACCACUGCUCUUCAUCCAGAGCAGGCAGCAGGGAUUCCCAGGUAUCCAAAGAAACCAAAACAGGCGGUGUAAUUUAGGACUGACUAAGUAAUGGCUCGGCCACUUUUAAGUGUGGAAGCAAAACUGACCCCACAGAUUUAGAAAACUGUAACACUGCUUAUUGGGAGAAACUAGUGUCACCCUGGCUAGUUCUGCUCCCCAAAUUCAAAGGUAAAUAAACGGUUGAGCAUGUCCGAUCA